GUUUUUCAGCUCACUUCAAGGGUACCUGAAGCGAAUUGGCACCAAAGCAGCAGCUGUAUUGCCGCAGUUCUAGCUUCACCUUCACGAUGUUUCCCUUGGUCAAAAGCGCACUAAAUCGUCUCCAAGUUCGAAGCAUUCAGCAAACAAUGGCAAGGCAGAGCCACCAGAAACGUACACCUGAUUUUCAUGACAAAUACGGUAAUGCUGUAUUAGCUAGUGGAGCCACUUUCUGUAUUGUUACAUGGACAUAUGUAGCAACACAAGUCGGAAUAGAAUGGAACCUGUCCCCUGUUGGCAGAGUUACCCCAAAGGAAUGGAGGAAUCAGUAAUCAUCCCAGCUGGUGUAAUAAUGAAUUGUUUAAAAAACAGCUCAUAAUUGAUGCCAAAUUAAAGCACUGUGUACCCAUUAAGAUAUGGCAUUAUUGAAGAAAUAAAGUACAUUUGAAACCUUCAUUGUAGGUUUUGUUUCUUUGUAAAUGAAACUAAGCUUGAUCACUUUAGCCUUUAUGUUAAUAUUAAAGUCAAAUGCUGUGCAGCUUCUUAAAUAGGUUUUUUUUUUUUUUUUUUUUUUUUUUUGGGACGAAGUCUCACUUUGUCCCCCAGGCUGGAGUGCAGUGGCACCAUCUCAGCUCACUGCGACCUCUGCCUCCUGAGUUCAAGUGAUUCUCCUGUCUCAGCCUCCCGAGUAGCCAGAACUACAGGCACAUGCCAUGACGCCCAGCUAAUUUUUUUUUUUUUUGAGACGGAGUCUCACUCUGUUGCCCAGGCUGGAAUGCAAUGGCGUGAUCUCGGCUCCUGCAACCUCCGCCUCCCGGGUUCAAGCGAUUCUCCUGUCUCAGCCUUCCAAGUAGCUGGGAUUACAGGUGCACGCCACCAGGCCCGGCUAAUUUUUGUAUUUUUAGUAGAGACGGGGUUUCACCAUGUUGGUCAGGCUGGUCUCGAGCUCCUGAUCUCGUGAUCCACCCACCUUGGUCUCCCAAAGUGCUGGGAUUACAGGUGUGAGCCACCGUGCCCGGCAAUUUUUGUAUUUUUAGUAGAGACAGGGUUUCACCAUAUUGGUCAGGCUGGUUUCAAACUCACGACCUCAGGUGAUCCGCCUGCCUUGGCCUCCCAAAGUGGUAGGAUUACAGGCGUGAGCCACGGCACCCAGCCCUUAAAUGGCUUUUAUGAGGUAAUGUGAAAGGAAAAUUUGCCUUUGACCUGGAAGUCAACUUUAUAGUAAGCUGAAAUUAUAAAUAACUGAUCAUGGAACUAUUGCAGAUCACCUUUGAGCCAAAAAUUUGGCCUGGAUUUUGGUUAUGCCUACUACUAUGUGCCUCUCAUUUGUAUUUAUACCUGGAAUUGGCAUUAUUAACUCCUUUUCACUCCUGCCUAGAAAACUUAAAGUGUCACCAGACCCAAGGGCGGAGUGGUCCUAUAAAACAAACUCGUAGCCUGUCUGAAGACUAGCUACUAGCUCCUUGGCUGUUUUGGCAUAUUCAUCUUGAUUAUAGCUCUUGGUCUUUCAUCAUAUUAGGGAUGUUUAUGAUGUUAUUAAAGAAAAUCUUGUCAAAUGCAGUCUGUUCCUAGUUAUCUACUAUCAGUCACCUGUUGUAUAAUUAUAACAAUGUUUGGAUUUGUGGAUUAUUAUUUUAGUAUAUAACAUUGGAUUUUAUGUAUGUUACCUGAAGAAGAGCAAUAUCUGUACCACAUAUUUCUUUGUUUUUCUUUUUUGAGAUGAAGUCUCACUCUGUUGCCCAGGCUGGAGUGCAGUGGUGUGAUCUUGACACACUGCAACCUUUGCCUCCCGGAUUCAAGUGAUUCUCCUGUCUCAGCCUCCCUAGUAACUGGAAUUACAGGCGCCUGCCACCAUGCCUGGCUAAUUUUUGUAUUUUUAGUAGAGAUGGGGUUUCACCAUGUUGGCCAACCUGGUCUUGAACUCCUGACCUCAGGCGAUCCACCCACCUCAGCCUCCCAAAGUGCUAGGCUUACAGGCAUGAGACACCGCGCCCGGCUUAUAUAUCAUUACUUUCUUGGCUGAGAGCUGUAGUCUGUGGUAGUUGUUUUGUUUUGUUUUUUGUUUUUUUUUUGUAGUUUUCUUGAUCGUGAUCAAUUAAGCAGAAAGUAGAAUUUCAGUCAGGUAACCUGUCUAUAUUAGCUAAAUUAUCUUUUGCUUAUUACAUAGAGUGCUAGAAGUAUGCUGUCAUGGCAUAUGUCCUAGUUUCUCAUCAAAUGGACCAAAGUCAGUGAUUUUAUUUGAAGAGGAAAAAUUGAACGUCAUUGUAAAUUAAGUUGCAAGUUUAGUAACCAUAUUGUACCACUGUUUGAUAAAUUUGAACGCUUUAUGGUAUUUCAUAUUUAGAAUGUUCAAAAUAGUACUGAAGUAUUCAAAUACAUACAACCCUGAGCGAUAUUGAAGUAAAAUAAACAUGUAUUUAAGGAAGUGUCAACCUUCAAUUAUAUAC